GCACACCCGGAAGCGGCGGAGUAGAGCGGAGCCUGGCGGGCGUGGGAACCCAGGCCCCGCCGAGGCGGCCAGGUUAGUGCAGCAGGAGGUGAGAUGGCAGCUGGGCAAAAUGGGCACGAAGAGUGGGUGGGCAGCGCAUACCUGUUUGUGGAGUCCUCGCUGGACAAGGUGGUCCUGUCGGAUGCCUACGCGCACCCCCAGCAGAAGGUGGCAGUGUACAGGGCUCUGCAGGCUGCCUUGGCAGAGAGCGGCGGGAGCCCGGACGUGCUGCAGAUGCUGAAGAUCCACCGCAGCGACCCGCAGCUGAUCGUGCAGCUGCGAUUCUGCGGGCGGCAGCCCUGUGGCCGCUUCCUCCGCGCCUACCGCGAGGGGGCGCUGCGCGCCGCGCUGCAGAGGAGCCUGGCGGCCGCGCUCGCCCAGCACUCGGUGCCGCUGCAACUGGAGCUGCGCGCCGGCGCCGAGCGGCUGGACGCUUUGCUGGCGGACGAGGAGCGCUGUUUGAGUUGCAUCCUAGCCCAGCAGCCCGACCGGCUCCGGGAUGAAGAACUGGCUGAGCUGGAGGAUGCGCUGCGAAAUCUGAAGUGCGGCUCGGGGGCCCGGGGUGGCGACGGGGAGGUCGCUUCGGCCCCCUUGCAGCCCCCGGUGCCCUCUCUGUCGGAGGUGAAGCCGCCGCCGCCGCCGCCACCUGCCCAGACUUUUCUGUUCCAGGGUCAGCCUGUAGUGAAUCGGCCGCUGAGCCUGAAGGACCAACAGACGUUCGCGCGCUCUGUGGGUCUCAAAUGGCGCAAGGUGGGGCGCUCACUGCAGCGAGGCUGCCGGGCGCUGCGGGACCCGGCGCUGGACUCGCUGGCCUACGAGUACGAGCGCGAGGGACUGUACGAGCAGGCCUUCCAGCUGCUGCGGCGCUUCGUGCAGGCCGAGGGCCGCCGCGCCACGCUGCAGCGCCUGGUGGAGGCACUCGAGGAGAACGAGCUCACCAGCCUGGCAGAGGACUUGCUGGGCCUGACCGAUCCCAAUGGCGGCCUGGCCUAGACCAGGGGUGCAGCCAGCUUUUGGAGAACCUGGAUGGCCUUAGGGUUCCUUCUGCGGCUAUUGCUGAACCCCUGUCCAUCCACGGGACCCUGAAACUCCACUUGGCCUAUCUGCUGGACCUGCUGGGGCAGAGUUGAUUGCCUUCCCCAGGAGCCAGACCACUGGGGGUGCAUCAUUGGGGAUUCUGCCUCAGGUACUUUGAUAGAGUGUGGGGUGGGGGGGACCUGCUUUGGAGAUCAGCCUCACCUUCUCCCAUCCCAGAAGCGGGGCUUACAGCCAGCCCUUACAGUUUCACUCAUGAAGCACCUUGAUCUUUGGUGUCCUGGACUUCAUCCUGGGUGCUGCAGAUACUGCAGUGAAGUAAAACAGGAAUCAAUCUUGCCUGCCCCCAGCUCACACUCAGCGUGGGACCCCGAAUGUUAAGCAAUGAUAAUAAAGUAUAACACGGAUUUUGAUGUGAGAAA